ACUGAGAAGAUUCAAAACCUACAAAAGCCUGCCACUGACAUUGAAGAACCAAUAUAUACAAUGGACAAACAAUCCAGUGCCGGCGGGGUGAAGAGGAGCGUCCCCUGUGAUUCCAACGAGGCCAACGAGAUGAUGCCGGAGACCCCAACUGGGGACUCAGACCCGCAACCUGCUCCUAAAAAAAUGAAAACAUCUGAGUCCUCGACCAUACUAGUGGUUCGCUACAGGAGGAACUUUAAAAGAACAUCUCCAGAGGAACUGCUGAAUGACCACGCCCGAGAGAACAGAAUCAACCCCCUCCAAAUGGAGGAGGAGGAAUUCAUGGAAAUAAUGGUUGAAAUACCUGCAAAGUAGCAAGAAGCUACAUCUCUCAACCUUGGGCAAUGAAAAUAAAGUUUGAGAAGCUGAUGGCUGUGUA